GGACGGAGGGACGGGGGCUCAAGGGCGGGUCGGGUGGGGUCCCGACGCCCCCUCCUCGGCUGGGCGCACCCCGGGUGUCCGCAGGGAGGGGCGAUGUUCUGGGGGGGGGAGCGUCUGCCCGACGCCCCCUCCCUCAGGAGCUCCUUCCCUUAACAGAGCUGAGAGAGGCAUCUGGAGCUGCAGCAUGGACCAGCGAGAGCCCCUGCCUCCCGCUCCUGCAGAAAAUGAAAUGAAAUAUGAUACCAAUAAUAAUGAAGAGGAAGAGGGAGAACAGUUCGAUUUUGACAGUGGAGAUGAAAUCCCAGAAGCGGACAGACAGGCCCCAUCCGCCCCUGAGACAGGAGGUGCUGGAGCCAGUGAAGCCCCUGCACCCACAGGAGGUGAGGAUGGAGCUGGAGCAGAAACCACCCCAGUGGCAGAGCCUACUAAGCUGGUGCUCCCGAUGAAAGUCAACCCAUAUUCUGUCAUCGACAUCACGCCAUUCCAGGAGGACCAGCCGCCCACCCCCGUGCCCAGCGCUGAGGAGGAGAAUGUGGGUCUCCAUGUGCCCUGCGGGUACUUGGUGCCUGUACCCUGCGGCUAUGCGGUGCCCUCCAACCUGCCCCUCCUGCUGCCCGCCUACUCCAGCCCGGUCAUCAUCUGCGCCACGUCCCUGGACGAAGAAGAAACACCAGAAGUCACAGAAGAUCGCCAGCCCAAUUCUCUGAGUUCCGAGGAGCCUCCAACCAGUGAAGAUCAAGUCGGUCGAGAGGACAGCGCACUUGCCCGCUGGGCCGCAGACCCGGCCAACACAGCCUGGAUGGAGAAUCCAGAGGAAGCAAUUUACGAUGACGUUCCAAGGGAAAACUCAGACUCUGAACCAGAUGAAAUGAUUUAUGAUGAUGUUGAGAAUGGGGAUGAAGGUGGAAACAGCUCCUUGGAAUACGGAUGGAGUUCGAGUGAAUUUGAAAGUUACGAAGAGCAGAGUGACUCGGAGUGCAAGAAUGGGAUUCCCAGGUCCUUCCUGCGCAGCAACCACAAAAAGCAACUUUCUCAUGACCUAACCCGUUUAAAGGAGCACUAUGAGAAAAAGAUGAGAGAUUUGAUGGCAAGCACGGUGGGCGUGGUGGAGAUUCAGCAGCUCAGGCAGAAGCAUGAACUGAAGAUGCAGAAGCUCGUGAAGGCCGCGAAGGACGGCACCAAGGACGGGCUGGAGAGGACCAGGGCAGCCGUGAAGAGGGGCCGCUCCUUCAUCAGGACCAAGUCUCUCAUCGCACAGGAUCACAGAUCUUCUCUUGAGGAAGAACAGAAUUUGUUCAUUGAUGUUGACUGCAAGCACCCGGAAGCCAUCUUGACCCCGAUGCCCGAGGGUUUAUCUCAGCAGCAGGUUGUAAGAAGAUAUAUACUGGGUUCAGUUGUCGACAGUGAAAAGAACUACGUAGAUGCUCUUAAGAGGAUUUUGGAGCAAUAUGAGAAGCCGCUGUCUGAGAUGGAGCCAAAGGUUCUGAGUGAGAGGAAGCUGAAGACGGUGUUCUACCGAGUCAAAGAGAUCCUGCAGUGCCACUCGCUAUUUCAGAUCGCGCUGGCCAGCCGCGUUUCCGAGUGGGACUCCGUGGAAAUGAUAGGCGAUGUCUUCGUGGCUUCGUUUUCUAAGUCCAUGGUGCUGGAUGCAUACAGUGAAUAUGUGAACAAUUUCAGCACAGCCGUGGCAGUCCUCAAGAAAACAUGUGCCACAAAGCCCGCUUUUCUUGAAUUUUUAAAGCAGGAACAGGAGGCCAGCCCCGAUCGAACCACGCUCUACAGCCUGAUGAUGAAGCCCAUCCAGAGGUUCCCACAGUUCAUCCUCCUGCUCCAGGACAUGCUGAAGAACACCUCCAAAGGCCACCCCGACAGGCUGCCUCUUCAGAUGGCCCUGACAGAGCUCGAAACACUAGCAGAGAAGUUAAAUGAAAGAAAGAGAGAUGCUGAUCAACGCUGUGAAGUGAAGCAAAUAGCCAAAGCCAUAAACGAAAGAUACCUGAACAAGCUUCUCAGCAGUGGAAGCCGAUACCUCAUUCGAUCAGAUGAUAUGAUAGAAACAGUUUACAACGACAGAGGAGAGAUUGUUAAAACCAAAGAACGCCGAGUCUUCAUGUUAAAUGAUGUGUUAAUGUGUGCCACCGUCAGCUCACGCCCCUCUCAUGACAGCCGUGUGAUGAGCAGCCAGAGGUACUUGCUGAAGUGGAGCGUUCCACUGGGACAUGUGGACGCCAUCGAGUAUGGCAGCAGCGCAGGCACGGGCGAGCACAGCAGGCACCUUGCCGUUCACCCGCCGGAGAGCCUGGCCGUGGUUGCUAACGCGAAACCAAACAAAGUUUACAUGGGGCCAGGACAACUGUAUCAAGAUUUACAAAACUUGUUGCAUGACUUAAAUGUAAUUGGCCAAAUCACUCAGCUGAUAGGAAACCUUAAAGGAAACUAUCAGAACUUAAACCAGUCAGUAGCCCAUGACUGGACAUCAGGUUUACAAAGGCUUAUUUUGAAGAAAGAAGAUGAAAUCAGAGCUGCGGACUGCUGCAGAAUUCAGUUACAGCUUCCCGGGAAGCAGGACAAAUCUGGGCGACCGACGUUCUUUACAGCUGUGUUCAAUACGUUCACCCCUGCCAUCAAGGAGUCCUGGGUCAACAGCUUACAGAUGGCCAAGCUCGCCCUAGAAGAGGAGAACCACAUGGGCUGGUUCUGUGUGGAAGACGAUGGGAAUCACAUUAAAAAGGAGAAGCAUCCUCUCCUCGUCGGACACAUGCCCGUGAUGGUGGCCAAGCAGCAGGAGUUCAAGAUUGAAUGUGCUGCUUAUAACCCUGAACCUUACCUAAAUAAUGAAAGCCAGCCAGAUUCAUUUUCCACGGCACAUGGUUUCCUGUGGAUCGGAAGUUGCACCCAUCAAAUGGGUCAGAUUGCCAUCGUCUCGUUUCAAAAUUCCACUCCCAAAGUCAUUGAGUGCUUCAACGUGGAAUCUCGCAUCCUGUGCAUGCUGUACGUUCCCGUCGAGGAGAAGCGCAGAGAGCCUGGGGCACCCCCGGACCCCGAGACCCCGGCCGUGAGAGCUUCUGAUGUCCCCACGAUCUGUGUAGGGACGGAGGAGGGAAGCAUUUCCAUUUAUAAAAGCAGUCAAGGCUCCAAGAAAGUGAGACUUCAGCACUUUUUCACUCCUGAGAAGUCCACAGUCAUGAGCCUGGCUUGCACGUCUCAGAGCCUGUACGCUGGCCUGGUCAACGGGGCAGUCGCCAGCUACGCCAGAGCCCCAGAUGGAUCCUGGGAUUCAGAACCUCAAAAAGUGAUCAAGUUAGGCGUCCUACCAGUUAGAAGUCUACUCAUGAUGGAAGACACGUUGUGGGCGGCUUCCGGAGGUCAAGUCUUCAUCAUCAGUGUGGAGACUCAUGCUGUAGAGGGUCAGCUGGAGGCCCACCAGGAGGAAGGCAUGGUGAUCUCCCACAUGGCCGUGUCCGGCGUCGGGAUCUGGAUUGCCUUCACCUCAGGGUCCACGCUCCGCCUUUUUCACACGGAAACUCUCAAGCACCUGCAGGACAUCAACAUCGCCACCCCUGUUCACAACAUGCUGCCAGAGUUCCGAGAGCAGCCACGGAAAUGCAGCGGCCCUGCAGGAUCCUUGGUGUUUAUCCCUCUCCGGGUGGGAUCAGAAAGAAACUCCUAAUCAAGGGAAGGCUCUGGCAAGUGUGAGUGGAGUUUGUAUUUUGAAUUUGAUUUCUUAAUAAAAUAACCCUUGCACACGAUUUAAUAAAACCCAACAGCACUCACGCCCAGGCUAUGAAAAGCAAAGCAGGAUAGGAAAGCCUGCGCUCUGGGGACUCACAGCCCCGCCCCCAUCCCAGCACCCCACCCACUGUCAGCACCCAACCCUGCCCCCAUCCUCACACCCCACCCCGCAUUCAGCACCCACCCUCUCAUCCCAGCAUCCCACCCACUGUCAGCACCCGCCCCGGCCCCCCGCACUGUCCCCAUACCCCACCCCGCUGUCAGCUGCCUCUCCCGCCCGCCUCCCUACUGCUGCUGCUCGAAAGCCACUCCUGUAUGGCAGGUUCUUGAUGCUUUGUUUUAGAUACUGUCUUUGACCUCUCCUGUAGAAGAGAAAGAUGGAAUUAUCCUGCUUCCCUCCAAGCAUAGAGCACCCAACACAGUCCUGCACCCACCCAGAAACAGAAUGCAGACCCCUUGCCGGCUGCUCAGGUCGCAGGUUCUGGCUAAAUCGCAGCUGCCUGUGUUGCGUGUUUUGGAUGAUGAAGUUGUCUGUGGCUGGGCGCUGAGCCUUCCUUGGGACUUUUCACCCUUCAGCUCAUAGUUUCCAGGCGGCCGAUGAUGGAUCCAUCCCAAGCCCACCACAAGCCUCUCACUUGGCAGCAGAUGCAUGGGGCUCUGCAGAGCCACCAUCCCCUGGCGCCCACUCUCCCGGGCCCCUCCAACAUCCUGGGCUGGCUCUCCAUGGCCACAGUGCGUGCUCUCAGCCCCCUGCUCCGGGGGCCCCUGAAUCGUGGGUCUUUACUUAUUCCUACACGACAUAGUCAGGUCUGCAUUUUAGACCCGCAUGAAAGCAAACACAUGAGUCUGUCCAGAUGGAGUGCCGUGCUUCUCGUUGGCAGGUUUCUCCGGCAUUUCGGUACUAAGUUGGAAAUAGCUCCAGCUUCACUGAUUUCUGGGGUACACUGACUGCUUUACCCACAUUCAGUUCUCUGCUCCCAGGCUGUGGUCUGCUGCCACCGUGGCCUUGUCAGCAGGAGAAAGGUACACGGGUUAGAGGCAACCUCGGUGACACCAGAAGUUCAGUUUUGUUUGUGAUGCUUCUGACAGUGAUUCUCUGUAAGAUCCUCAGUGCGGCAUAGACUGAAAUGGUUCUGAUUUUCAUUGCAUUUUGUGACUCAGAGGGAAUGAGCAGGCCAGAGAGUCCUUUCCUCCAGAGAGUCCUUUCAUCUCAUCUCCUCUGUCUAGUCGUCUUUGCCUUUCAGCUAAUAUUUCAUAUAUUUCAUAGAAAUAAGCAUUAUUGCAUUUCAUGCUGUAUUUAGACAUUCCGGUGGGGGCAUGCUCAUACCGUGCUGAAGUGCGCGGAUGCUGAGGUCGCCGGGCCGUCACUGCUCCUGGGUUCUUCUCCUCCUUAUCGUCCAAGAUGGUUCCUGGAGGCCCACACAUGUCCUCUGUGCUCUGUUCGCACACACACAAAACCUUCAUUCUAGAGUUGUAUUCAUGACGAUGCUCAAAUGGGUUUUCAUGUGUGUGUGUGUGUGUGUGUGUGGCAACAAGACAUAAAAUUAUCUUUUUGUGCUAUUGCUGGAAUAUAAAAGUCAGGUAGCUUCUGCAAAUGAAGACUUGCCAAGCCGAAACAACAAAAUUUGAAAAAAACAAACUGUAUUAUAACUCAUGCCUUUUGUGUAAGUUCACACAACGUGAUGAAACCUCCUUCCUUCCUCAGGGUCUCAGCACGCUGGCCCCUGGGGAAUCCGUGAAUCUGUAGCUAAGGCCCUGGCUUUUCUCCUUCUAUUUGGAAUUCACUUCUGAAAACCAUUUAGCUCACGUUCUUUCACAUAAGCUACAUCAGAUUCAACACAGACUAACAGUUGAUGAAGGUCUGUGAUUAACAUACACAUUCGUUAGAGCGGUCGUUACCUUUCUAAGUUAUAAAGGAGUAGAGUUUACAGCGAGUGAGUUCACGGCGCCUCAGCUUUUAGGUUGUGAGCAGUUGCAGUAGGUUACAUCACCAGGCAGAUGUUUCCUGCUCUGUCCCGCAUGUUCAAAGGAGGAUAUUUUUGAUGGGAAAGUGCUGAGACACAUGGUAAAUUGCGCCUUUCUGAGUCUCCACCGAGCGAAUACAGAGCCUCCAGGAACUAUGUGACCAAAUAAAAUGGCCAAAAUUUCCAUUAGAAAAAAAAAGACAAAAAACGUGUAACUUUUCUGAAGACCAUGGACUACACCGUAAGGGAAUUCAGUAAAUGAAACCGGACUCAAGAUGGUGAGUUAACGAACGAGACUGAGGACUUGGGAGCCACAGCCUUUCUCGGUGGCCGGUGUGGCCCUGGCCUGUCCUUUGUUUUAUGUUCCAGGCUGGGAAGAGCAGAGGGCGAAUCCCCCUGGUAGCAUUCCCUCCCAUACUUGGGGGACGUAUUGCUUCUUCUACUCACUGUUCUGUCUCUGAGGUUAUUUGAAUGAACCUGGAUGGUGUUGUUUACACCCCCAGCUUCUCCCAGCCUCCAGGGCGGGAGAUGCGUCUGCCUCUGUGGCUGCCUGCAGAAGGCCCUGGUGACUCCCCACGGAGUCACCAUCCAGCAGCCGCUCAAGUGCAGUCAGUCCCACUUCACACGUGUAACCCAUUUACCAACCUCACUGUGCAGCUGCAUCACCGUUCACCACCUCAGCUGCCCCUGCCUCCCACCUCGCCAGCGGACCUCACGUGGGCUCCAACUCCCGGGACCCAGCCCCAUCUGGGACACGCCCUGCUGUCCUGUUCUAGGUCACUGUUGGUGCUUCCGGACGGGCACGGGACGCCUGGAUAGCGGCACUCACCGCAGCCUCUGGAAUCGGAAAAUGACCGCAUGACCUCGUGACUGUGGCCCUCAGCUUUCCCAUGUAAAAUUAAAGAUGUUGAUUGGCAGACUGCUUGGAAAAUGCAAUGGAAAA